CCAUUGUGACCCCAGAAGUUGACAAAGACUCCUCCAAACUUCUCAUUUAACAUCUCAUGGAUGUUUGAAAACAUAACAUAAUCUGUGAUAUUUCUUCUGUCGCUAGUCACUGUGUUUAAAUUUUAAAGUAGUGAAUUGUACCAGUGUUAAUCCAAAGAAGAAUUAAGAAUUAUUUUUCCCUCACACCUGGAAUGGCAGUGAACAUGGCUGGAGUUGAUUGGCUGUGAGUGCCUUGGGCUCUAUGAGAGAUUCAUUAGGGGAUCUCCAUUCCUCAUCCUGCUCUACAGGGUCAGCCUUGUGGUGACUUUAUGGUCAAGCCCACCAGUGGUCAGCUUGCAAGUCCAAACAGGACAGAACAUGUGUGGCCCAGCCUGAAGGAGGCACCCGUUGGUCUGGGGCUCUCUGACUUGGACUUCUUUCUUAGGUCAGGGACAUGAUUGGCUUGCAUUUGACCGCACACACAGCAUCUUUUUACAGGGAAGGGAGAUGGCACCAUCUCCUCUGGCAGGGCAAGCUGAAGUCUGCAGUCCUUCCCUUGCUUUUUUAUUUUUUUGAGACAGUUUUGCUCUUGUUGCCCAGGCUGGAGUGCAAUGGUGUGAUCUCAGCUCACUGCAAGCUCCGCCUCCUGGGUUCAAGCGAUUCUCCUGCCUCAGCCUCCCAAGUAGCUGAGAUUAUAGGAUUCUCCUGCCUCAGCCUCCCAAGUAGCUGAGAUUACAGGCAUGCGCCACCAUGCCAGGCUAAUUUUGUAUUUUUAGUAGAGAUAGAGUUUCACCACGUUGGUGAGAUUGGUCUCAAACUCCUGACCUUAUGUGAUCCACCCACCUCGGCCUCCCAAAAUGCUGGGAUUACAGUUGAGAGCCACCACACCUGGCCUGUUCACUUGCUUUUUUGCAGGGGAAUGGAUGUUGUCCCCCCAGGUGCCUCUAAGGAAAAGCAGCACAGAAUCCUCACCUCAUUUCCACCAAACGCGGCUGGUCCCUUCCAAGAAGAUAUUUGAUUCCUCUCAGCCCAAAACAUGACUUCAUGCUUGUGUUCUUUUUCUUAAAAAUAAUAACAAACUUACGUUACAAAAGUAUUAAUACAAUUUUUUUUUUUUGUUUUUUUGAGAUGGAGUUUCGCUCUUGUUGCCUAGGCUUGGAGUGCAGUGGUGCAAUCUCGGCUCACCACAGCCUCCGCCUCCCUGGUUCAAGCAAUUCGCCUGCCUCAGCCUCCCGAGUAGGUGGGAUUACAGGCAUGCACCACCACACCAGGCUAAUUUUGUAUUUUUAGUAGAGAUGGGGUUUCUCCAUGUUGGUCAGGCUGGUCUUGAACUCCUGACCUCAGGUGAUCCGCCUGUCUCAGCCUCCCAAAGUGCUGGGGUUACAGGCGUGAGCCACCAUACCCAGCCACAAAUUUUUUAAGAAAUUGAAAUCAUAGAAAGUGUGUACUGUCAAUCCCUUCCCAGGUCUCAAAGGCCAAAUGUAGCUCCUGGUAACAGUUUGAUGUCUACCUUUUCAAACUUGAGUUUCUCUACACACACACACACACACACACACACACACACACACACACACACACGGACACAGUUAUUUAGUUUUGGUAAAAUGUAUUCAUACUAACUUUUUUUUCAAAAUUUGUUCCCUCAAUAUAAUAACAUAAACUUCCAUGAACGAUGGAUGCAUAAUUCUUUCUUAUCUUUUUAAUGGCUGCAAAAUAAACUCGAAGCUCCAUUUCCUCUGCAAAUAAACAAGACCAUUGCCCACUAUACCCAGUUUGGGGAGGCUGGUGGGCUCCAGUCUACUUUCCUGCUUCUGCAGUUGGGUUUUGUGUUGUUAGUGCUGUGUGCUCUGAAACCUGCUUAUGGGAGUUGUGUUUGUUAUUGUACAGACAUAGCUUUCUUUUCUUUUCUUGUUUUAGAGACAGAGUCUCACUCUGUUGCCCAGACUGGAGUGCAGUGGUGUGGUCAUACCUCACUGCAGCAUUGAACUCCUGGACUCAAGUGAUCCUCCCACUUCAGCCUCUAGGGUAGCUUGGACUAACAGGUUCAUACCACCAUAUCUGGCUAAUUUUUAAAUUUUUAUCGUUUGUAGAGACAGGGUGUCACUGUGUUGCCCAGGCUGGUCUCGAACUCCUGGGCUCAGGCGAUCCACCUGCCUUGCACAGCCAAAUUGCUGGAAUUACAGGCAAGAGCCACCACACCCAAUCAGAAAUAGUAUAAAUGACAUAAUCUAUAAAUUCAAUGGGUGUAAAGAAAGGAAAAACUCAAGUUGACUGAUUUGAAAAUACAGGAUGAGGAAAACUUUUAAAGAUAAUUUUUGUUGAAUUAGAUAUGAGUCAUAAUGAAAAUUGAUUAGGGUUUUGUAUUCAGAUGCAUAGGUGCAUUUAGACACUUUAAGAAAACCAAACCAGGAAACAGAUGAAAUAUGUGAUUUGUGAAGAAAUUAAUGUGAACGGCAAUGAGUAGAUUUUUUACUCAAAGAAAGGGCUGGGCUGCACAUCUGUUGAUUGAUUAAUGAUGGUUCAUUUAUUUGUAUUACGUUAAAAAUAUUUAUUGUGGGUGUGGAUCAUUAUUUAUAGUACCUAACUAUCAUUUUUAAUGUUUCCAUUAAUGAACAUUCAUAUGAAUGAAGAUUCGUAUGGAUCUUGGUUAUAUCCGUAGGAAGGCGUCAGCUGGUCCAGUUCCAGAAUAUGACUGUGCCUUCAUUUCAUUGCUCCCUGCUCUAGUUAUUUACAACUUUCUUUCCCUUGGUUUCAGGUAACCUGGAAAUAUUCACAGAUUACACCUGAGCUCACAGCCUUCUUUGAGAUGUGUGCUUUUUUUUUUUUUUUUUUUUUUUUGAGACGGAGUCUCGCUGUGUCACCCAGGCUGGAGUGCAAUGGCGUGAUUUUGGCUCACUGCAACCUCCGCCUUCUGGGUUCAAGUGAUUCUCCUGCUUCAGCCUCCCGAGCAGCUGGGAUUACAGUUGCAUGCCACCAUGCCCAGCUAAUUUUUGUGUGUGUGUGUUUUAGUAGAGACGGGGUUUCACCGUGUUGCCCAGGCUGGUCUCGAACUCCUGAGCUCAGGCAAUUCAUCUGCCUCAGUCUCCCAAAGUGCAAGGAUUAUAGGCGUGAGCCACCGUGCCCAGCCAACAUGUCUGCAUUUUAUUACAAAUGUGCCCAUACACUUCUGAGAAGGGUAGAGCAUGUUAAUCUGUAUGUCUCACUCUGGCUGCACUCCGCGGAAGCGACUGCCUGUGAAGUUUAAUUGGCUUGGAGGUGGGACAGUGCCAUGAUGUCUAGUUAACAUAUAUUUAAGUUAUACCUUGAGGUCAUUUGAAAAUGGAAUUCUCCCUAGUGCCCAGCUAGUGUUUAUCCUCUGAUGUUUCUAAUCAUUUAGCCAUUUAAAAUAGGGAGAUGAUGAGACACUUGGAAGGCUUUUAAGAAAUUAAUCUCCCACUUAGCUUUUUAUAAUGUUAAUUAAUGUCUAUACCAAACUCAAAGCAAACAUUAAUGAUGUAAUAAUCUAAGUAGUCUCUUUAAUAUCAAGGCUAAUUCAAAAAGCCUUGUAUGAGGUUGCUCAGCAAGUCUUGUCAGUGUAUUAAGACAGGAAACAGAAACAAGGGGCGAGCUAAUGGAUUGUAGAAGAUGCAAUUACUAUUUUUAAGAGAAUAUGUGCUUUAUUUAUUUAUUUAUUUGAGACAGGGUCUUGCUCUGUUACUCAGGCUGGAGUGCAGUGGUACAAUCUUGGCUCAGGGCAGCCUCUUCCUCCCGGGUUCAAGUGAUUCUCCCUCCUCAGCCUCCCGAGUACCUGGGAUUACAGGCGUGCACUACCACGCCAAGCUAAUUUUUGUAUUUUUAGUGGAGAUCGGGUUUUGCCAUGUUGGCCAGGCUGGUCUCGAACUCCUGAACUCGAGUAAUCCACCCACUUCGGCAUCACAAAGUGCUGGGAUUACAGGUGUGAGCCACCGCACCCUGCCGAGAAUAUGUACAUUAAAGCCCAAGUAAAUAGACUAAAAACUUUUAGAAUUAAUUUGUGAACUUACUAAUGAAUUUACAUACAAUAUAUUGGAGAAGAUUUCCUAUGUAUCAUCAAUAAUCAGAAGAUGUACAGGGGAAACAUUCCAUUGCAAAAGCAAAAUAGAUAAGCCACACCACUGUACCAUCAAAAAUAUGCAGGUGCUGUUGAAGUUACCUAAAAACUUCACCAAACAAUAAGAAAGUAUGUAAGAAUAAUGAAAUUUUCAAAAGUACAAUAAUUUAUUUAUGCUCUGGAAGACUGAAUGUUUUAAAGAUGUCAGUUCUUCUGAAGGUAGCAAACAUUUAAAAUAACCCCAGUGGGACUUUUCAGGGAUGCUGGACAAAAGGAUCCUAUGACUCAUUUGGAGGAAUAAAGAAAUGGCAAAUGCCAAAGAAAAUUUUGAGUCUGAUAAAUGGUGAAAGGAGAUCUUUACUGUGUUUUCAAAUACAUAAAAAAGCUGCAAAAACUACAACAACAUGGCACUGCCCAAAAUGAUGGAUACUGAUAGGAGAACAGGCAAAGGAGACAAAUACAUUUCUUCAGAAGAAAACUACUAUGGUUGUUAUAACAAUUUUAAAAGUCCUGAGAAUCAUUGAUUCCAGAACUAGAAAUUAAGCCUACCGAUGGAACACGUUUUGGUUAUCAAAUUGAACAAAAUUAUAUUCUUAGACACUGCUGAUCGAUCUGUACAUUGGACCGAUCUGUACAUUGGACUGAUCUGUACAUUGGACCAGUCUCUUGAGGGAACGUUUUGGGCCAUGCAUCCUGAACCCACCCCCUGCUCCUUGGACCCAGUACUUUCACUUCUAGGAAUCCGUCCUGAGUAGAUGGGAAGAGAAAUAAAGAUUUACAGAUGGAAGUGUAUCAUAGCUUUAUUUGGUGCAGUUGACAAUUAGAAAUGAACCUAGUGUUCAGAAGCAGGAAAAUACUUAAGUAGAUUUCAUAAGCUACAUAGAGAAAUGUUUAUUUAUUUAUUUACGAGUUGGGGUUUUACUCUUGUUGCCCAGGCUGGAGUGCAAUGGUGUGAUCUCUGCUCACUGCAACCUCCGCCUUUUAAAAGUCACAUUAAAAAAAAAUGAUAUAGCAAAACCUUCAAAAUGUAAUAUUCAUCUAUAAUGAUAUGGGAAAAUUUUUAUAAUAUAAUGUUGAUUUAGUCAACUAAGCUAAGCUCACAGGAGAUACUUGACUACAUAGAAGAAUUGGGUUCCUUAUGGAGCAUAUAGUUAGGGGGCAAUAUAACAAAAUAUUAUUAAUAUUAUAUUAAAAGUUAAUGUAGCAGGAAGUUCAAUUUAUGAAAUGAGUCUAAUCGUGUAACAAAAAGUGAACUAUAGAGUGCGUAUAUAGUUAGGGAAGUCAGAAGGCCAUGCGUCAAUGCUUUAAUAAUGGUCUUGUCUGGUAAACAUAUGGCAGAUGAUUUUUGUUCCUUCAUUAUUCUUUCUAGCACUUUCCCAAUUUUCUGUAAAAGCUGACUUGCAUUUUAAUAAUCAGAGCAAAGUUAUAAAAGAACCUUCAGAGUCUCCCCUUCUCAAAAUGUUACUGGAUGCAGUACAUACACAUUUACAAAAGAUCACAUUCUUUUUUCUUUUUUCUUUUUUCUUUUUUUUUUUGAGACGGAGUCUCUCUCUGUUGCCCAGGCUGGAGUGCAGUGGCGCGAUCUCAGCUCACUGCAAGCUCCGCCUCCCGGGUUCACGCCAUUCUCGUGCCUCAGCCUCCCGAGUAGCUGGGACUACAGGCUCCCACCACCACGCCCGGCUAAUUUCUUUUUGUAUUUUUAGUAGAGACGGGGUUUCACUGUGUUAGCCAGGAUGGUCUCGAUCUCCUGACCUUGUGAUCCGCCCGCCUCAGCCUCCCAAAGUGGUGGGAUUACGGGUGUGAGGCACCACGCCCAGCCACAUUUAUUUAACCCAGUAACUAACCACUGAUUUCUGCAUAGUUAUGCUGGUACAAUGGCAGGAUCAUGUAAUUAACCAGUAUAUUUCUUUUUGUUGUUGUUGUUUUUUAAGGAACACAAAUAAAAAUGUAAGGUUUACGUCAAGGUUAAAAACACGAUGAAAUAAGAAAGGGGGUCUGGAGUAUGUGUGGAGAUAUACCUGGGUAUAACAAUGAAAUGGCGUGAUUGCUGGUAGAAUGUUCACUAUGCCGCACCAUGUUCUAUGCUCCAUACAUUCAGUCCUAUGAAUGGGAAGGGCUCAUUUCCCCCAUUCUGUAGAUGAGAAAACUGAAGCCUGGUAGUCACGCUUCUUGGGAGUAUCCUGGGUAGCCCUGGCCAAGGUGGGCUUUGAACCCAGGGAGCCUGGGCUGUUAACUACAAAACCACAGGAUACGUACAACAUAAGACAUCGACAUUCCUUGUCCAAAUCGCCAGCAGGCAGGGGGGCGAAGCCACCCAGUGAGAGUUCCUAAGAGCCAGAAAGGAGGAGACCCACACUCCUGCUGGAUCAAAGCUGAUGUAAGUCAGCAUUAAAGCUUUUCAUUGGUUUAUUCGCCGAUGGAAGGACCUUCUCUUUCUUUCUCUUGCCUCAGAAUCAGUGUUUGCCCAAGACAGCAAUUUGUGGAAAUGGAGAAAAUCUGAGAAUUCUUCUGUGGCUUUGCUAAAUUGAGGCUUGUCCUCCACAGUCCAUCCUACCCUCCCCCACUUUUUUUCCAGCAAAAUAAGUGAUAGUUCACUCACCUUCUAGGCAUAAGAGUCAUCCUUUCUCUGUGGUCAAACCAGUUCAGAGCUGACUCAAAAGUCCUGUGACUUGUUGAAAUACAACAUUGGAUGUGUGCCCCCUGUUCUCUCCCGGCAUCCCGAAUACUGGCGUUGGGAUGUUUCCUGACACCCACCUUCUCCCCCUGCCUGGGUCUCAGGCAGAUGUUCCUGUCCAAGUCUUUCUGCAUCGUCUGGGCAAUGGCAGCUGUCCAGGUCUUCCAAGUGCAAGAUCUCAGGAUGGUUUCACAAGUACAUUGCACUCUGUUUUAUGUUCUCACCACAGGGGAAUUAGAGGUGAAUUACAGGUGAGUGGAGCCCACCGGGUGCCCCACAAGUUUGACACCUUCGCCCCAGGUGUCCAGGUGGGUGAAUAGCCCAUCACAUGCCCCGCACUUCCAGGGAGAGUCUCUCCUAGCACCUGGGAGCAUCUGCUCCCAAGUGGGGUGUGGCUCGAGCAAGCUUUAACUUUAUUGCGUGUCCUCAGCCUUCCCUGAUUACCGAAGGCUUUCUUACGUAUCCUGGGAGGGGCGCCUUGCUUUAAGGGCUUCUGUGUGUUACAGACAUGCUGCCAGCGGUGGAAACAGAUGUGUUUUUCUUGUUGGCCCCCAUGUCUGAAAGACACAUGUUAUUUGUCAUUGGCUUACUUAAGGCCACAAAGAAACAUUGACAGCCCAGCCCUGUGGCCUGUCUGACUUGGGAACAGGACCCAAGCCCAGAUCGCCCCCCUUCCUUUUCAUUUCCUUGGGGCCAGCGGGCCGGGGGUGCCCUGUGGGCAGCGCUGUUCACUAGGUUAAGGGGGCCCUGUUUUGUCAGAGAAGAAAAUACAGCUGGCAAGAGGCCUUGCCCGUCACCCCCUCCUGCCAGGGCAGGCUGUUUCCUAAUUGCAAACACAUGGGCUGGUUCCAGAGCGUGGGGACGGAUUCCAUGUCCCGCCUGGGAGAGCUGUGUGUGUCCCACCCCGAUGCCCUGUUUCUCAUCAAGGAAAUGGGGGUGUUGCAUACCAGGGCCAGAGGACAGCUGCCUCGGGUGGGGGAGUUCCCGGGCACUCCCAGAUGUGCCUGCUGGGAACAUUUUUGGUGUGCGUUGAAACAUUGGGAUUUGGUUGCAUUUCAUCGUCCUCUGUUUCCUACUACAUUUUUGGUGAAGUGGAGGUUCUGGAUCCGAACGACCCUUUAGGACCCCUUGAUGGGCAGGACGGCCCGAUUCCAACUCUGAAAGGUUACUUUCUGAAUUUUCUGGAGCCAGUAAACAAUAUCACCAUUGUCCAAGGCCAGACGGCAAUUCUGCACUGCAAGGUGGCAGGAAACCCACCCCCUAACGUGCGGUGGCUAAAGAAUGAUGCCCCGGUGGUGCAGGAGCCGCGGCGGAUCAUCAUCCGGAAGACAGAAUAUGGUUCACGACUGCGAAUCCAGGACCUGGACACGACAGACACUGGCUACUACCAGUGCGUGGCCACCAACGGGAUGAAGACCAUUACCGCCACUGGCGUCCUGUUUGUGCGGCUGGGUCCAACGCACAGCCCAAAUCAUAACUUUCAGGAUGAUUACCACGAGGAUGGGUUCUGCCAGCCUUACCGGGGAAUUGCCUGUGCACGCUUCAUUGGCAACCGGACCAUUUAUGUGGACUCGCUUCAGAUGCAGGGGGAGAUUGAAAACCGAAUCACAGCGGCCUUCACCAUGAUCGGCACGUCUACGCACCUGUCGGACCAGUGCUCACAGUUCGCCAUCCCAUCCUUCUGCCACUUCGUGUUUCCUCUGUGCGACGCGCGCUCCCGGACACCCAAGCCGCGUGAGCUGUGCCGCGACGAGUGCGAGGUGCUGGAGAGCGACCUGUGCCGCCAGGAGUACACCAUCGCCCGCUCCAACCCGCUCAUCCUCAUGCGGCUUCAGCUGCCCAAGUGUGAGGCGCUGCCCAUGCCUGAGAGCCCCGACGCUGCCAACUGCAUGCGCAUUGGCAUCCCAGCCGAGAGGCUGGGCCGCUACCAUCAGUGCUAUAACGGCUCAGGCAUGGAUUACAGAGGAACGGCAAGCACCACCAAGUCAGGCCACCAGUGCCAGCCGUGGGCCCUGCAGCACCCCCACAGCCACCACCUGUCCAGCACAGACUUCCCUGAGCUUGGAGGGGGGCACGCCUACUGCCGGAACCCCGGAGGCCAGAUGGAGGGCCCCUGGUGCUUUACGCAGAAUAAAAACGUACGCAUGGAACUGUGUGACGUACCCUCGUGUAGUCCCCGAGACAGCAGCAAGAUGGGGAUUCUGUACAUCUUGGUCCCCAGCAUCGCAAUUCCACUGGUCAUCGCUUGCCUUUUCUUCUUGGUUUGCAUGUGCCGGAAUAAGCAGAAGGCAUCUGCGUCCACACCGCAGCGGCGACAGCUGAUGGCCUCGCCCAGCCAAGACAUGGAAAUGCCCCUCAUUAACCAGCACAAACAGGCCAAACUCAAAGAGAUCAGCCUGUCUGCGGUGAGGUUCAUGGAGGAGCUGGGAGAGGACCGGUUUGGGAAAGUCUACAAAGGUCACCUGUUCGGCCCUGCCCCGGGGGAGCAGACCCAGGCUGUGGCCAUCAAAACGCUGAAGGACAAAGCGGAGGGGCCCCUGCGGGAGGAGUUCCGGCAUGAGGCUAUGCUGCGAGCACGGCUGCAACACCCCAACGUCGUCUGCCUGCUGGGCGUGGUGACCAAGGACCAGCCCCUGAGCAUGAUCUUCAGCUACUGUUCGCACGGCGACCUCCACGAAUUCCUGGUCAUGCGCUCGCCGCACUCGGACGUGGGCAGCACCGAUGAUGACCGCACGGUGAAGUCCGCCCUGGAGCCCCCCGACUUCGUGCACCUUGUGGCACAGAUCGCGGCGGGGAUGGAGUACCUAUCCAGCCACCACGUGGUUCACAAGGACCUGGCCACCCGCAAUGUGCUAGUGUACGACAAGCUGAACGUGAAGAUCUCAGACUUGGGCCUCUUCCGAGAGGUGUAUGCCGCCGAUUACUACAAGCUGCUGGGGAACUCGCUGCUGCCUAUCCGCUGGAUGGCCCCAGAGGCCAUCAUGUACGGCAAGUUCUCCAUCGACUCAGACAUCUGGUCCUACGGUGUGGUCCUGUGGGAGGUCUUCAGCUACGGCCUGCAGCCCUACUGCGGGUACUCCAACCAGGAUGUGGUGGAGAUGAUCCGGAACCGGCAGGUGCUGCCUUGCCCCGAUGACUGUCCCGCCUGGGUGUAUGCCCUCAUGAUCGAGUGCUGGAACGAGUUCCCCAGCCGGCGGCCCCGCUUCAAGGACAUCCACAGCCGGCUCCGAGCCUGGGGCAACCUUUCCAACUACAACAGCUCGGCGCAGACCUCGGGGGCCAGCAACACCACGCAGACCAGCUCCCUGAGCACCAGCCCAGUGAGCAAUGUGAGCAACGCCCGCUACGUGGGGCCCAAGCAGAAGGCCCCGCCCUUCCCACAGCCCCAGUUCAUCCCCAUGAAGGGCCAGAUCAGACCCAUGGUGCCCCCGCCGCAGCUCUACGUCCCCGUCAACGGCUACCAGCCGGUGCCGGCCUAUGGGGCCUACCUGCCCAACUUCUACCCGGUGCAGAUCCCAAUGCAGAUGGCCCCGCAGCAGGUGCCUCCUCAGAUGGUCCCCAAGCCCAGCUCACACCACAGUGGCAGUGGCUCCACCAGCACAGGCUACGUCACCACGGCCCCCUCCAACACAUCCAUGGCAGACAGGGCAGCCCUGCUCUCAGAGGGCGCUGAUGACACACAGAACGCCCCAGAAGAUGGGGCCCAGAGCACCGUGCAGGAAGCAGAGGAGGAGGAGGAAGGCUCUGUCCCAGAGACUGAGCUGCUGGGGGACUGUGACACUCUGCAGGUGGACGAGGCCCAAGUCCAGCUGGAAGCUUGAGUGGCACCAGGGCCCGGGGUUCGGGGAUAGAAGCCCCGCCGAGACCCCACAGGGACCUCAGUCACCUUUGAGAAGACACCAUACUCAGCAAUCACAAGAGCCCGCCGGCCAGUGGGCUUGUUUGCAGACUGGGUGAGGUGGAGCCCUGCUCCUCUCUGUCCUCUGACACAGAGAGCUGCCCUGCCUAGGAGCACCCAAGCCAGGCAGGGGGUCUGGCAGCACGGCGUCCUGGGGAGCAGGACACAUGGUCAUCCCCAGGGCUGUAUACAUUGAUUCUGGUGGUAGACUGGUAGUGAGCAGCAAAUGCCUUUCAAGAAAAUAGGUGGCAGCUUCACUCCAUGUCAUAUAUGGAGUGAAUAUUUCAAAACGUUGGGAAUAAGGGCCUGCAAAAGGCAGCGAGGAGGCACCUCGGGUCUUGAGGUUCCUGACAACCGAUCUGGUCUGUUGGUUUGAGGAUGAAGGGGCUCCAUUUCUGCUGCCUCCCUGCUGAGAAUAUUCUCCCUUUAGCAGCCAAAGAUUCGCUGGAACGGAGGCUGCCCUCUGCUGCCUGUUGGGGUCGGAAGACAAGGGGCUUCUGAAAUGGGAGUUCCUGAGAUACAACAAAAUGUGUGCCUUCAAAGAAACUGACAGCUUUGUAUUUGGUGAAAUGGUUUUAAUUAUACUCCAUGUGUAUUUUGCCCACUUUUUUUGGGAAUUCAAGGGAAAGUGUUUCUUGGGUUUGGAAUGUUCAGAGGAAGCAGUAUUGUACAGAACACGGUAUUGUUAUUUUUGUUAAGAAUCAUGUACAGAGCUUAAAUGUAAUUUAUAUGUUUUUAAUAUGCCAUUUUCAUUGAAGUAUUUUGGUCUUAAGAUGACUUUAGUAAUUUAACUGUUUAUGUUACCCACGUUGGGAUCCAGUUGGUCUUGGUUUGCUUCUCUCUGUACCACGUGCACAUGAGGUCCAUUCAUUUUACAGCCCCUGUUACACACAGACCCACAGGCAGCCGUCUGUGCCCCGCACACAUUGUUGGUCCUAUUUGUAAAUCCCACACCCGGUGUAUCCAAUAAAGUGAAACAAAGCA